AGAUGAUACCAGAGAGCAAGAGAGAGGAACUGGGGUUUGCGAACCUUGUGGCUUUGUCUGUUUCCUGUUUCAGCAAGGCUGCUGUGCAAAAAGAAAGACGGUACCAAGAAGGGACGUGUUAAUGGGGCCCAGACCUAUGGAUUGAAAGCGUGUGCUUUACCCAUCUGCUGUCUUGCUCCAUCUGAGACCAGAGCCAAGAUCUGCCCAGGACUGGAAUGCUUUCCCGAGUGGCUUGAGUUGGAGCCUGGGACUAGGAGCAGCCUUAUUGAGGUACAAUUCAUGUGCUUGUGGGUUUGGAUGGCACAAUCUGUGUCUGGGCUAAGGAAAGCAGACUUGGCACCAACAUUAACCCUGACAGAUCCAGGCAUCUAUUCCAGGAACUGGAAGCCAAGCGCAACAGGUGCUUGGAGGUCAUCAUGAUCAGCCCAGACCCCAGGCCCUCCCCUGGCUUGGCCCGGUGGGCUGAGAGCUAUGAGGCCAAGUGUGAGCGCAGGCAAGAGAUCCGUGAAAGCCGCCGCUGCCGUCCCAAUGUGACCACUUGCCGCCAGGUGGGGAAGACGCUGAGGAUCCAACAGAGAGAGCAGCUCCAGAGAGCUCGACUGCAGCAGUUCUUCAGGAGGAGGAACCUGGAGCUAGAGGAGAAGGGCAAAGCGCAGCAUCCCCAGGCCAGGGAGCAAGGGCCCUCCAGGCGGCCAGGACAGGUGACUGUCCUCAAGGAACCCUUGUCUUGUGCCAGAAGGAUUUCUUCUCCCAGAGAGCAGGUGACAGGCACCAGCUCUGAAGUCUUUCCAGCCCAGCAUCCUCCUCCCUCAGGCAUCUGCAGGGAUCUGUCUGACCACCUCUCCUCACAGGCUGGGGGCCUUCCUCCACAGGACACUCCCAUCAAGAAGCCACCCAAACACCACCGUGGUACUCAGACAAAGGCAGAAGGACCAACAAUUAAGAACGAUGCCAGUCAGCAAACCAAUUACGGAGUUGCAGUUCUGGAUAAGGAAAUCAUCCAGCUUUCUGAUUACCUCAAAGAGGCCCUACAAAGGGAGCUGGUCCUAAAACAGAAAAUGGUGAUUCUCCAAGACCUACUGUCCACUCUGAUUCAGGCCUCUGACAGCUCUUGGAAGGGACAGCUUAAUGAAGACAAACUGAAGGGGAAACUGAGAUCCUUAGAAAACCAGCUAUACACCUGUACCCAGAAAUACUCCCCUUGGGGAAUGAAAAAAGUACUACUGGAGAUGGAAGACCAGAAAAACAGCUAUGAGCAGAAGGCCAAGGAGUCACUGCAGAAAGUGCUGGAGGAGAAAAUGAAUGCAGAGCAGCAACUACAGAGCACACAGCGAUCCCUGGCCCUGGCAGAGCAGAAGUGUGAAGAGUGGAGGAGCCAGUAUGAGGCUCUGAAGGAGGACUGGAGGACCCUUGGGACCCAGCACAGGGAGCUGGAGAGCCAACUCCACGUGCUUCAGUCCAAACUGCAGGGAGCAGAUAGCAGGGACUUACAGAUGAACCAGGCCCUGCGAUUUUUGGAAAAUGAGCACCAGCAACUGCAGGCCAAGAUUGAAUGCCUGCAAGGGGACAGAGACCUGUGCAGCUUGGAUACCCAGGACCUACAAGAUCAACUAAAAAGGUCAGAGGCAGAGAAACUCACCCUGGUGACCAGAGUACAGCAGUUGCAGGAGGCAGCGGGAUGGACUACAUGACCUCCUGGAGUCCCAGCCAGUUCUGGGAGUCUGUUAAGUCCGGGAUGUGUGGGAGCUUUUUAAGGACUGAUCAUUGGCUCUGAGGACACUUCAACUAGUUAGCCUUCUAUCUUGAGGUAUAUAAACUGUGAAAAAGGGUUUCUAUUCUCUCUGAAAGCACAUGUCUGUGUUGAACAUUUCAAUAAAUUUAUUUUGAACUCAGGAUUUCAUGUCAAUUUUUACACACUUGAUUUUCCAAAUCACAUCCAACUCCCCAGCCCCAAACCACAUAGCAGUCCAGAGUCAACUCACUGUUAGCCCUAGAGAGUCUACUGUCCAUGUUUCCUGAGAAUUCACUGUGUAUACAGAGGGGCAAUAGCUCCUCACCUGUCCACUACACACGACCUUUUGUUUUCUCUUCACAAUCAUUGGGCAUAAUAUAAUAGAUAAGGCAGAAAUUUUUAUGCUCACAGAGUAUGGAUAAGAACAUGAAAGUCUAUGGUGACACAAACUAACAACACAGCUAUAACAACAAUCCAAAACUUCUGACUCCUAGUCCAUGCUCUUUUCACCAAGACUAAGACUGCAGGGUGGCUAAAAAACCAUCUUUAACCAUAUGAAGAUAAAUUUUAGGAUAUGACUGCCAUCUUCACAACUUUCAAAUGAGGACAUCAGGGAAAAGGGAUUGUAUUAAAGCAUUUACCAAACUUAUUUGACAAACUAGGAAGAAUGUGACAUACAACCAAUGAAAUUCAAUUAAGAAGUAUUCACUAAAACUAUCUAGCACUAGAUAAGACUGGGGAUACAAAGAAAAGAUCCCAAUCUUGCCCUCAAGGAGCUCAGAUUCCAGCUGUCUGUCCAAGCUUAGCAGGGGCCUACUGGAAGUUAACCUUUAUGUCAGAGAAUGCCAUCAGUCUAGCCAAGAGCACGCCCUCCCAAGUUCCCUCCCCUCUCCCCACUCCUAGUGGUUUCACCCUCAGGGCCCUUCCUCAGAGGUGUGGGCCUCACUGUCACCAAGAAUCUGGCUGCUUUUUUAGAUCAGGCUUUGCCCGUGUGGAGUCCAAAGUCCUUCCCUAACGAAGUGGAGCCUGAGGGUACAGGGAAGGAGAAAGACUGGGAUCUCAGAGACCAGCUGCAAAAGAAGACUUUGCAGCUCCAGGCCAAGGAAAAGGAGGUGAGAGGGUGACCUGAGAUAGUGAGGGCUCAUUUGCGAAAUAGCAGAGAAACCUGGGAGGCAGUCAAAAAGCAGGGAUUUCAAAGUUUAAGUUGUGAGUGGAUAACCACAGACAUUCAUUUGCCUACAUAAAGUGUCUGUGCUUUUGGGCUGACUUGUCAAUCUUUUCCCUUCCUUAUUUAUACCAACUCCUAUUCAAGGUUUUAUUAAAUGAUUACCUUUUAGAAAGUCGACCAAAACUCAAACACAUUUAAUAAAAAUAUUAACUUCUCAAUAUGUCGUCCCACAUUGAGUAUCUUAAGUCUUUAUAUGUCUCUUAAAGAGUAAAACUCUUCCUUUGUACAUACUCACAAACAUACACAUCCCCAGAAGUAUUGAUAUGCAACUAGCUCCUGGGAAAGAAACUUGUACUAAGGUCACUUCUAGGUCGUUUGUUCUAUAAGAACUUCAUUUUUCGGUGUCUCUCAUUUGCAAAGCACUUGCACGUAAAGUCAUAUAAAAGAACUUAAAUGUAUAAAAUGUAAUACUAUAAUAUGCAUUACUGUCAAUCAUUUAAAUGAACACAUUCCAGACAAUGUAAGACAGUCAAAAGACAAACUCAAAUCCCUGAGAAUGGCUGGGAAGGGAAGAUGGUGGUAAAAAUUCCAAAUGAGUGAAACUUACAAAGGGCAGUCUCCCCUGCCUGGGCUCUGUCCUAGACAGAAGUGACAGUGAUGACUUUGGUGAUGUUCUCCCCAGUGCAGAGAACUGCAUUCAGAAUUAGACAACCUCAGUGACGAGUAUCUCUCCUGCCUGCGUAAGCUGCAGCACUGUCGAGAAGAGCUGAACCAGAGCCAGCAGCUGCCUCCCAGAGUAAGAGGGUCUCUCCUUCCCAUAAAGCCCUGGAUGAUGGGACGAUUCCUUCUUUAACCAAGUUUUGCACAUAAAAUAUAUCAGCCCACGCCAACAACUGGCCAUCCUGUCCCACUGUGCUUGGUUUAUACUAUACUGACAUUAUGGCAACCAUUGAAAAAAACACUGGCUCGUCCAUCAAAGCCCAACUUUCACAGAACUCUCAAUGCCAGAAGGAAAGACUUACUCUUAGCUAAAGUAUGAAAGGGUGUUCUUUUAGCCGAUGAUAAGCAUGGUGGCAAGAACAGAAGGACACAAAAGUACUGGGGAAUACAAAGAAAGAAUAUAAUUUUGCUGGGUUAUUUUCCACCCUUCAUUAUUCAUAUCAGUAUUUAUAUAUCUGGUCCCUGAUGGAUACGGCUCCCUGGGCCAGAGAACAUUGGUUAAGUGGUUUUAUCCCAAGACAGGUGACAAAAUGGGAGACAGAGUAAAAAGCUUUUUCUCCACCACCAACCCAGCGUUUUCCACUGGGCUAGAGUAGGAAGAAGAAAGAUUUUUGCCUAUAUCUUUUCCAAUCCACUCAUGGCCACUUUCUUCUGUCUCCCUGUCCCCCUACAGAGGCAAUGUGGGCGAUGGCUCCCAGUGCUGAUGGUGGUGAUUGCUGCAGCACUGGCAGUGUUCCUGGCCAAUAAAGACAACCUGAUGAUCUGAAUAAUUUGUGACAACUGCCUUGGGUGAAAAUCAGAAGCAAGCAACUCAGCGAAAAACUCAGAAGGUUUGGGUACAUUACAGCUUGGGUUUUCCAACUGACUUAGGAUUUCUGACUUUUUAUUAAUUUCUUAACCUACUGUAAAUAAACUUCACCUGACCAGA